UUUUUGUAUUUUUAGUAGAGAUGGGGUUUGACCAUGUUGGCCAGGAUGGUCUCGAUAUCCUGACCUUGUGAUCCACCUGGCCUUGGCCUCCCAAAGUGCUGGGAUUACAGGCGUGAGCCACCAUACCCGGCCCACUCUUUUGUAAUAACACUUAGCUUAAAAUGCUAAUGUGUUGUAUAGCUAUAUAAAAAUAUUUUCUUUAUUCCCUUACAUUAUUCUAUAGCUUUUUCCUGUAAAAAUUUUUUUUGUUGUUAUAAACUAAGACACACACAUUGUGCCUACACCGGGUCAGGAGCAUCAAUAUCACUCUUUUCUUCCUCCACAUCUUGUCCUACUGGAAGGUUUUCAGGGGCAGUAACAUGAAUGGAGCUGUCAUCUCCUAUAAUAACUGCUUUUUUCUGGAAUACUUAUAAUUGUCUAGUAUUAUGUACAGUACAUCAUUGUAAGCAUUAUGCUUGUAUAUGACUGGCAUCCCAGGUUUGUUUACACCAGCAUUACCACAGACAUGAGUAAUGUGUUACACUACAAGUUAUGAGGGCUACAAAGUCAAUAGGAAUUUUUCAGCUCCAUUAUAAUCAUCUGAGACCAGUAUCAUGUGUGCAGUCGCUGUUGACCUAAAUGUUAUGUAGCAUGUGACUAGCUGAUGAAUCUUUGAUUAUGGCUGAAUGUUCUCAUUCAUUGCAGGAAAAAAAUAUCCUCCAAAUCACUAGGUAGUAUGUAAGUGACCAAAACUUUUUUCCAUUUUAUGUUGGAGCCAAAUCAUUAGUGUUAGGAUAAAUUACUUCUUUAUGUAUGUGCUCUAAAAUGAAAAGUUAUUUCUGAAUAUUAAAGCAUAUGUAUUAAGAGUAUAAAAACAAGAUACAGAUUUUGGUGUGAAAUAUAUCUUAUGAUUCAAGUCAUAAUUUAAAUAGAAUUGAAGAUGAUGUGAAAUCACUGGGCUGGAAGUAGCUUAUACCUUGAUUAGUAAGAGGAAGCCCGGGAUCAUCCUGUGAUGGUACCACUGAUGAAAUUAUGACCAGGUGGGCCCGAGUUAGUACCACAUAUAACAAGAGACCCUUGCCUGCAACAUCAUGGGAGGACAUGAAGAAGGGAUCCUUUGAGGGAACAAGCCAAAACCUACCAAAGCGUAAACAACUUGAAGCCAAUAGGCUAUCCCUCAAAAAUGAUGCACCCCAAGCAAAACAUAAAAAGAACAAAAAGAAAAAAGAGUACUUAAAUGAAGAUGUGAAUGGAUUCAUGGAAUACCUAAGACAGAAUUCACAGAUGGUUCACAAUGGGCAAAUUAUAGCAACAGACAGUGAGGAAGUAAGGGAAGAAAUUGCAGUUGCUUUAAAGAAAGACAGUCGACGGGAAGGAAGAAGAUUAAAAAGACAAGCGGCAAAGAAAAAUGCAAUGGUGUGUUUCCAUUGUAGAAAACCUGGUCAUGGAAUUGCAGAUUGCCCCGCCGCCCUUGAAAAUCAAGACAUGGGCACUGGGAUAUGUUACAGGUGUGGGUCCACAGAGCACGAAAUAACCAAGUGUAAGGCUAAAGUAGACCCGGCUCUUGGCGAAUUUCCUUUUGCAAAAUGUUUUGUUUGUGGAGAAAUGGGGCACCUGUCUAGAUCUUGUCCUGAUAAUCCCAAAGGACUCUAUGCUGAUGGUGGCGGUUGCAAACUUUGUGGCUCUGUGGAACAUUUAAAGAAAGAUUGCCCUGAAAGUCAGAAUUCAGAGCGAAUGGUCACAGUUGGUCGCUGGGCAAAGGGAAUGAGUGCAGACUAUGAAGAAAUUUUGGAUGUACCUAAACCGCAAAAACCCAAAACAAAAAUACCUAAAGUUGUUAAUUUUUGAUAACAGCUAGCACUAUCAUGAGUUACUACCUCAUUGUUACUUUCUAAACCAGGCCCGCUUCACGAGUUAGAGUUGAGCUCCCCUGUAGCCAGGACUAUGCUGUAGAUAUCAGUAUGAUCUGGGUGUGGCCAAAAACAAUUUUCUUUAUUCUGUCUAUCAAAUAGUACUUCUACCACUGUUUGGAGAAAAUUGAAGAAAAGAAUAAGAUGAUUAAAUGAAUUCUCUAAAAGAACAUAUUUUAAGAGACAGAACUUAGACAUAACCAAGUAGUUGUAUACCUGAUUGUAACAAUCAUCUUUUAUAAAAGCAAAAUUAUGCAUAAAUGUAAAACACCCCUAAACAAAGGGAACAAAUGAAUUUUUGGUUAUAUUGUUUUCUUGGCUCAAAGUAUCAAUUUAUUAUUAUAAUAGAAAUUUAUAAGUUGCUAGAAAGUCUAUAUUUUUAAAGUACGGAAUAAAAAUAUGUUUUCUAUUAAGCAAUAGAAAUAUUUUUGUGUAUAAUUUUUCUGAAUACUUGAUUCUCGAUUGAAAUAUCCAUUGUUCGUUAAUAUCCAUGUAACAAUCCCAUUGGAAACAAGAUUUUUUUUGAAUCCUAGAUGAGAAUAAACAGGGAUUUGGUUUUUGUUUUAGUUUUGA